GGAAAAGCUCGAUAAUUACCCAGCCUAACCAUUUCUCAGGUGCUUGCGAGGUGAUCAGAAGGCAAAGAUGUCGGAGCGAAAAGUAUUAAACAAAUACUACCCGCCGGACUUUGACCCAUCAAAGAUCCCCAAACUCAAGCUCCCCAAAGACCGGCAGUACGUGGUGCGGCUGAUGGCCCCCUUCAACAUGAGGUGUAAGACGUGCGGAGAAUACAUCUACAAGGGGAAGAAAUUCAAUGCUCGGAAGGAGACGGUGCAGAACGAGGUCUACCUGGGCCUGCCCAUCUUCCGCUUUUACAUCAAGUGCACGCGCUGCCUGGCAGAGAUCACCUUCAAGACAGACCCUGAAAACACAGACUACACCAUGGAGCAUGGAGCCACGCGGAAUUUCCAGGCUGAGAAGCUCCUGGAGGAGGAGGAGAAGAGGGUGCAGAAGGAGCGGGAGGACGAGGAGCUGAACAACCCCAUGAAGGUGCUGGAGAACCGGACCAAGGACUCCAAGCUGGAGAUGGAGGUGCUGGAGAACCUCCAGGAGCUGAAAGACCUGAACCAGCGGCAGGCGCACGUGGACUUCGAGGCUAUGCUGAGGCAGCACCGCCUGUCGGAGGAGGAGCGGCGGAGGCAGCAGCAGGAGGAGGACGAGCAGGAGACCGCGGCCCUGUUGGAGGAAGCCAGAAAGCGAAGACUGCUGGAGGACUCCGACUCAGAGGAUGAGGCUGCUCCCUCGCCCCUGCAGCCAGCCCUUCGGCCCAACCCCACCGCCAUCCUGGAUGAGGCCCCAAAGCCCAAGAGGAAGGUGGAGGUCUGGGAGCAGAGCGUUGGCAGCCUGGGCAGCCGGCCCCCGCUGUCGAGGCUGGUCGUGGUGAAGAAGGCAAAGGCCGACCCGGACUGCAGCAACGGGCAGCCUCAGGCGGCCCCCACCCCAGGAGCCCCGCAGAACAGGAAGGAGGCCAACCCUACACCCCUGACGCCUGGCGCGUCCUCCCUGAGCCAACUGGGUGCAUACCUGGACAGUGACGACAGCAACGGCAGCAACUGAGCCCUCCCAGGACCCCCUCACGGGGUCAAAGUCACACGUCCAGCUUCAGCCACAUUGAGGCCAGCAUUGCUGGUGGUCAGGGCAGGAGGCCUUGGCGUGACUGGAGGCCGGACAGACAAGCGCCAGCGUGCUCCAACACAUAGGGCCACCAGGGGCCUCAGCCCCAGGAGGUCCCUUCUCUGUGCCCUCACCAGCCUCUCAACACCUCGGGGACCCCUGCUGCUCCUGCCCCCACCUGUCACUGUGCUUAGGGCUGCAACAUCCCUGGAGCAGCUUCCAACACUACUUCAGGGUGGCAGUGUUUGGGGCACUGGGCGAGCCUGCCGGCCUCUAGAUGGCCUCAUCUCUUCCUUCCACAAACUGUCUAGAACCAAUAAAAGGAAACCUGCCAA